GAUUACAGGCGUGAGACACCACGCCUGGCCUUACAUAGCUUUUAGAAUAUAUUAUCUCAUGCAGUUGUAUAAACUUAAAAUAUUGGUGGGCCCAAAAAAGGUAGAGAUAAUUUCAAUUAAUGGAUAGAUUCAAUGUGAUGGAUGGUGGAAAACUAAAAUAUUUGUAGAAAGGUGUAUUUUUGCCCCUAUCAAGGUUGAUUUUCAAACUAGAGUCUGUCAGUUUUCUUUACUCCAUUAUCAAGAGCAAGUUAAUGAGAUGGGUAGACCGAUUGCCAGAUCCAGUGUGGAAAAUGAUGUGUGGCUGCUUUAUAGAUUACUGAGCUUCUCUAAUGGAGUAAGUUUAUGCUACUGUGUUCAAAUGAUACAAACAGGACCUCUAGGAGGUUAUGUUUUAUUGAAUGUAAGUGAUUUAGAUGGCUAAAUCUACAUACCUAUAGAAUGCCUGUGCACUUUACAGUUUUUUCUGCUUAAGAAUGCAAGUUAUGUUAGAGUUUUGUUUAUAAAACUCAGGAAAAAGUCAGAGAUGUCUUUUUGUUGUUGUUGUUGUUACAAGUUUAAGGUGAGCACUAAGAUCUGAGGCAGGUUAUAAAAUAGUUGAUAGGCAUAGAAUGAGCACAGUCUAAUUUCUCCUUGCAGGAAUGAAUUAUUUGCAAUAAUUUGUGUAUGUCUUUGUGAACUCGUUAAAUUCUUUGAUUUGUUAGAAAGUCAUUAUGUAUCUCCAAGGCACAUUUCUUUUUCUUUCUGUCAAUAAUGGUGUACUAAAGAAUAGAAAAAAAAUUCUAAUUUUAAAAAGGCUCUUUGCCAUUCUAGUCUCUCAAUUAUUCAAGCCCUUCUUUUCAUUUCUUAAACCUCUUUUGUGUUACUUUUGAGUCAUUUAAAUGCUUAUUAGCACAGAGUGAGCACAAAAAGCCAGGAGGAAUUGAAUUCAAAUCAGCUUUCCUACCUGUCAACAAGUUUGUCGAGUAAAGUUUUGGCUAAAUUGAGUUUUGGGGUAGAAAGUUCAUGAAAAUUCUAUUUAUCCAUUUGUAGGUAAUCAAGGUUAUUUGCAUAAUAUUUGAACUGGCUGUAAUGAAAAAUGUUUGUUAAUAGAGUGUGCACUAAUCAUAUAGUGCAUAGUCUUGUUUGUUUCUUAUUGUUUUUAAAGUAAAUUCUUUGUAAGUUUUUAAAAGUAGCUCUUGAGUUUUUGUAAAUAGUUAAAUAGACUUGGAAAGGGGAAAUAAUUCGGCAGUUAAAACAAUUUCUUCCCUAUGCUAAAACUCUAAGGGAAAAAAUGGGUUUUAUUUUUCCUUAAUGUUUCUAUGUUAGAUUUAAAGGCCUUCGAAAUCAUAUUGUGCUGAUUCUUAGAACAUUAAGUUGUUGUUCCUAAAUUAAAGCUGGGAAGUGAAAAUUUAAUUCUGAAAGCAUCAGCAACAACUUGUCCUUCUCUCCUUGUGUGCUGCCAUUUUAGCUUGGAAGGCAUACGUGUAAGAGCAGUCUCUUUGUACUAUUUAGCUGGUUAUCCCUACACAAAAACUUCUGGCUUUGUAGUUCUCAGGGCUCUCUGCUAGGUUGUGUGGAGGAUAUUGAGGUGAAUUAGACAUGGUCCCUUGACAAUAGCGUACUGUUGUUUUUUUUUGUAAUUUGAUUCUUAACCACUUGAAAUUGAAUCUGCCAACUCCUUUCCCCCAAGUAAAAGACCUAAGGUGCUAAUCCCUACUCACUGAUGACAAAUGCUAAAUUGGAAGCAACAGCUUAGGAAUGCAAAGAUCCUUAUCCAAUUACAUUACAAGCUCUCUAAGCCAGUCAUGUUCAGCAUCAUCAGGGCGAUAGGAAGGCAAGAUCUCACUUUGGUAAGAAUGAUAGCGUAGUUUGAGUAAGUUUUAGAAAAUUCUAAAAUGCAAAGUUCAUUCAAGGAAAUAAAAUGUGGUAGGAGCUGAGAAAAUGAUUUGCUUUUGUUAAGUUCAACGCAUAAAGGUUUAUGUGGAUCAUGGUUAAGAGCACUGGCUUGGGAGUCCAUCAGAUAAAGAUUUGAAUCCCAGCUCCACAAAUAUGUGACACUGGACCUGCCUAAGCCUCAAUUUCCUCAUCUGUAAAAUGGGCAUAAUAAAAUAACCUCUCACAGGAUUUUGGGGAGAAUUAGAUGAGAUCAUAGAUAUAAAACGCUUAACCGAGUAUACAGCAAUGCUUAAUGUAAGUGGUAACAGAAAGUACAAGGCACUGUUUGCUGACCGAACCGGUGUUUUUGAUCCUGCCUAGGAGACUAAGUAAACCACCCAAAAAGCAGUUAAGUAUCCAGGGAAUGUUAUAUAUGAGUAAAUGCCACAAUAGAUGGGAAAGACAAUAAGGGCUGUUGGGGAGCGAGGAGGGCUAUGCUAUCAUAAGAAUCAGGUGAGCUAAGUGUGGGUUGGUAAUAAACAUGACCCACUGGUCUCAUGGAAAGUAUGACUUUUCCCUUAGCCGUUUACUUUAAGAAAGGUCAGUGUCCUGAAUGCAGUUUGUAUUUAGAUUCUUAUGCCAAGAUUUUCCCCAGAAAAUAAUCUUUAUGAAAAGAUGUUCAUGUCUAUUUUGGCAAGUUGGGUUCUGCUAGUUAAAAAGAUGCCCCUCCCGCCCCACCACAUCACCAUUAGAUUGUAGUUAUGCAAAGCUCCUUCAGUAAUUGGAGUUCCUAUUGGGGAAGAGACAAAGAGAUGAGCUGCUGAAAGAUGGUCACAUUUGGAACAAACAGGCCAUGGUCAUAACAAAGUCAAAUACUCUUUAUUUGAACCUUAUGAAGAAAUUUCUUACAGGCUGGACACAGUGGCUCAUGCCAGCACUUUGGGAGGCUUGAUGGGUGGAUCACUUGACCUCAGGAGUUUGAGACCAGCCUGGGCAACACGGCAAAACCCCGUCUCUAUAAAAAAUACAAAAAUUAGCCUGAUGUGGUGGCACACAUGUGUAGUCCCAGCUACUUGGGAGGCUGAGGUGGGAGGAUUGCCUGAGCCCAGGGAGGUUGAGGCUGCAGUGAGCUGUGAUCAAACUACUACACUCCAUCCUGGGCGACAGAGUAAGACCUUGUCUCAAAAAAAAAAAAAUCCUUACAGUUAUGGUUCCAUUAUUGACAUGCUGUAUAGGGUUCCUCUCUAGAAGUCUCUAAUCUACAGUGGUGGCAUCUCUCACUUCUGUGAAUCAUAAUGCAACUUUUGCUUCUCCUCAUAUUCACACACCACUCUUGACAGUUACCUAGUCUCUGAUCUUACAGGGUUUAUGAAUAAAACUAGAAGGCAAGAUGAAAUGAUCUGAGACCACAUAAAUCGAUAUGAUGAAAUUCUUCUGAUUGAUCUAAUGGGGAAUAGAGGGACUCACACAUUUUAGUGUGCAAACACACUUGUACAGUUCCUUUUUUGGAAGAAGAUAUGGCUAUCAAAGGGCAUGAUAGAUGCACAGAAAUUACAAUAGUCUGUGAUCAGCUCUCACAUCUUGGGUUUAUCUACCUUCCCCACGAGACUGUGAACUUCUCAAGGGCAAGGUCUGUUUUUUUAUUCACCUCUGCAUUACCAGGGGCUAGCACAGGGCCAGAACCUCAGUAGGAACUCAAUAAAUGCAUCUUUAUGCUGAACUCACUUUGUUUUCUGUGCUGCCGGAAAUUGCAUGCCCCCAGUGGCCAUUUUGAGUGCAAAGUGUUAUUUUAAGAUGCUCUCUAGAGAAAGCACUCUAGGCUCUGCUUACAAAUGUCUGAGAGGAAAGGAGAGCCGAAUGACUAGGGGAUCUGGAGAAAUUCCUAAGUGAAGGUCGUGGAGAAAUGAUGGGAAGGAGAGACUCACCUCUUUUUGAGUGUGCUACUUCUAUCCCAAGACUGUUGUUAUUUUUCAUAAGAAAAUGCUCAGAUGUCAUUGAGGCUGUAGUCUGACUGCAAUACUGCAAAAAAGCACUUUUGGGCUAAUCAUUCUCUUUCUGAAACCAGUAGUUGCCAUGUUCCUCCUUGUGCUGAAACUCAGUUUGGAGGAUGGGGUGGUGGUAGUGGUGGCGUGGUGGUGCAGGGAUGUUUUUGAAUUGGCUCUGUGCCCUACUGCUCAGCUUUCUGCCUGCUUUCUGGUAUCCCUCCCAGUGUGAUAAAGGAGAGAUUCUAUGAUGCCAGUGUUCACUUCAGACUUGCAGAAGAGACAUUCUUAGAAUUCUUAAGGAGAACUAGUUUCUAAAGUAAAAGAUUUACCGGUAAACUAAUGACCUUUGGUAUGGUAUUUAAGCAGAAGUAACCCAGGCUCAUUUUGCAUUGCUUACAGAUAAAUAUUAUGUGAUUAUUCUUGUGUCUUACACAUUUCUAAUGAUAACAUAAAUAUGCCUGCUAGUCAAAUGUGCUUUUGGAUACAUGAGUGGUUGGAUGGUUGAAUAUAUACAUUCAUGUACAUUUUUAUGUAUUUUAGUAUUACAAGCAUGGUUUUAUAUUUAUACACAUACAGUUACGAUGAUAAAAGAUCAGUCAUCCUGUACUGCGAAUGUACAGGAACCACCACAAAAUUGUAAAGUCUAAGUGGUGAUGCUAUUAGUGACCCUCAGUGAGGAUCCAUUGUUUCCUCUCUUUGGACCAAGAAGUGGACUGCAACUGAAUCUAUUCUGACGAGUUUCCUUUUUUGCUAUCUGUCCUUUCCACUUAUAUUAGAAAUAAAAUUAUCUCAAUUUAUGGAGCUGUGCAUUUCUUCCCAUUUGUAGAGUUUGCACAUAGAAAGCUCAUUGAGAUUUGGUCCUUAGUGGCCUGAGUAAGCAACGGAAAAGUGUACUGCAUCCCACACCAUGGUACCAAAAUUGGCAUUUUUAUUUUACUAGAGAUAGAAAAAUGCAAUUUAUUCUCCUUUAUGGGAUGAUAUGAAGCUUUCUUUUUCAAUAAAUGUUUUCAAUGAAGAAGAUAUUUGAUUUGAAGAAAAAUAUGAAGUAAAUGAUAAUACAGAUGGUGUGGCAAAUAUGAGGAUUAUAUGUGAAUAAGUUCGGGAAACUAAUAGAAACAAGGAUUAGGAGUUGGGAGACCUGGGUUUGAAUCCUGGUUCAGCUCCUAAUGUAGACAGAUGAACUUAGGCCUCUGAGCCAGUUUCCUGAUGGAUAAAGUUGAAAUGAUGGUAUUUUCCUUGUCUACUUGACAAAGCGUUUGGUAACAAACAGAAUGCAUAUGAAAGUGUUUUCUUAAGACUGCAAAGUGACCUUGAAAUGAAUUAACAAAAAAUACUAAUAUUAUUAGCAAGUUAUUCAAGAAAACUUAGGAGUCAGUGAAUGAAAACUUUUAAGAACAAAUCAUUUUGUUUUGUUUUGUUUUCCCCAUGGUGAAAACUGAGUUGGUUCCAAAUUUAGGUUGACGGUUUUCCUGUCACUACUUACGGGAAGAAGACUGAAACAUAUGCUCACUUCUCUCCAGAUUGCAUAAAUGCCUUCGCCUUUUACUUAGCACUGCUCCGGAACUGUAUGGAAGUUGCUAUUAUUUGAAUGUUUAAGGAAAAGGCCAAAGUUGUUGAGCCCCUGGACUAUGAGAAUGUUAUUGCCCAAAGAAAAACCCAGAUUUACAGCGACCCCCUCCGAGAUCUGCUUAUGUUCCCAAUGGAAGAUAUAUCUAUCUCGGUGAUAGGUCGUCAACGCAGAACGGUGCAGUCUACUGUACCAGAAGAUGCUGAAAAGAGGGCCCAGAGUUUAUUUGUUAAAGAGUGUAUUAAAACCUAUAGCACAGAUUGGCACGUGGUAAACUACAAGUAUGAGGACUUCUCUGGGGACUUUCGAAUGUUGCCAUGUAAAUCUUUGAGACCAGAAAAGAUUCCUAAUCAUGUAUUUGAGAUAGAUGAAGACUGUGAGAAAGAUGAGGACUCAUCUUCUUUAUGUUCUCAGAAGGGUGGUGUGAUAAAACAAGGCUGGUUGCAUAAAGCAAAUGUAAAUAGUACCAUCACAGUAACCAUGAAGGUAUUCAAGAGACGAUAUUUUUACUUGACCCAACUUCCUGACGGUUCAUAUAUUCUCAAUUCCUAUAAAGAUGAGAAAAAUUCAAAAGAAUCGAAAGGUUGCAUCUACUUGGACGCCUGCAUUGAUGUUGUUCAGUGCCCCAAAAUGCGCCGUCAUGCUUUUGAACUCAAGAUGUUAGAUAAAUAUAGCCAUUAUCUGGCUGCUGAAACUGAGCAGGAAAUGGAGGAAUGGUUGAUAACUUUGAAAAAGAUUAUUCAGAUCAACACCGACAGUUUAGUUCAAGAAAAAAAGGAGACGGUAGAAACAGCACAAGAUGAUGAAACUAGCAGCCAAGGAAAAGCCGAGAACAUCAUGGCAAGUUUGGAAAGGAGCAUGCAUCCGGAACUGAUGAAGUAUGGAAGAGAAACUGAACAACUAAACAAACUCAGUAGAGGAGAUGGAAGACAGAAUCUCUUUUCUUUUGAUUCAGAAGUUCAGAGGUUGGACUUUUCAGGAAUUGAACCUGAUAUAAAGCCAUUUGAAGAAAAAUGCAAUAAACGUUUCCUGGUGAAUUGCCAUGAUUUAACUUUCAAUAUCUUGGGCCAAAUUGGAGACAAUGCAAAAGGACCACCCACAAAUGUUGAGCCCUUUUUUAUCAAUCUUGCCUUAUUUGAUGUAAAGAACAAUUGUAAGAUUUCAGCAGACUUUCAUGUAGACCUGAAUCCCCCAUCUGUCCGUGAAAUGCUGUGGGGCUCUUCAACCCAACUGGCCAGUGACGGUAGCCCAAAGGGCUCUUCACCCGAAUCUUACAUUCAUGGAAUUGCCGAAUCUCAGUUACGCUACAUACAACAGGGAAUUUUCUCAGUGACGAAUCCACAUCCUGAAAUUUUUCUAGUUGCCAGAAUUGAAAAGGUACUACAGGGAAACAUUACACACUGUGCAGAACCCUAUAUCAAAAAUUCUGAUCCAGUAAAGACGGCCCAGAAGGUGCACAGGACAGCUAAACAAGUGUGUAGCCGCCUUGGACAAUACAGAAUGCCCUUCGCUUGGGCUGCCAGACCCAUUUUCAAAGAUACUCAAGGCUCUCUUGAUCUGGAUGGGAGAUUUUCUCCUCUGUAUAAACAAGACAGUAGCAAGCUUUCAAGUGAAGACAUUCUCAAGUUGCUCUCAGAAUAUAAGAAGCCAGAAAAGACCAAACUGCAGAUUAUUCCUGGGCAGCUAAACAUCACAGUAGAAUGUGUUCCUGUGGAUUUAUCAAAUUGUAUUACUUCUUCAUAUGUGCCCUUGAAGCCUUUUGAAAAGAAUUGCCAAAAUAUUACUGUGGAGGUUGAAGAGUUUGUUCCAGAAAUGACAAAAUAUUGUUAUCCAUUUACUAUUUACAAAAACCAUCUGUAUGUAUAUCCCCUGCAAUUAAAAUACGAUAGCCAGAAAACAUUUGCCAAGGCAAGGAACAUUGCAGUCUGUGUGGAAUUCCGGGAUUCAGAUGAAAGUGACGCUAGUGCCCUAAAGUGUAUUUAUGGAAAACCUGCAGGGUCUGUUUUUACCACAAAUGCUUAUGCUGUUGUCUCGCAUCACAACCAAAAUCCAGAGUUCUAUGAUGAGAUUAAAAUUGAGCUUCCCAUUCACCUACAUCAAAAACAUCAUUUGCUUUUCACUUUUUAUCAUGUAAGUUGUGAAAUUAACACAAAGGGAACAACCAAAAAGCAAGACACAGUUGAAACUCCAGUUGGGUUUGCCUGGGUACCUUUGCUGAAAGAUGGUAGAAUCAUCACAUUUGAGCAGCAGCUGCCAGUUUCCGCCAAUCUUCCCCCAGGCUACUUGAAUCUGAAUGAUGCAGAAUCAAGAAGGCAAUGUAACGUGGAUAUUAAAUGGGUAGAUGGUGCAAAGCCUUUGUUGAAGAUUAAAAGCCACUUAGAAUCUACCAUUUACACUCAAGAUCUGCAUGUGCACAAAUUCUUCCAUCAUUGCCAGCUGAUUCAGUCAGGCUCGAAAGAAGUUCCAGGGGAGCUCAUUAAAUAUUUAAAGUGUUUGCAUGCCAUGGAGAUCCAAGUCAUGAUACAGUUUCUACCUGUAAUUCUUAUGCAACUCUUCCGAGUUCUCACAAAUAUGACCCAUGAAGAUGACGUUCCUAUCAACUGCACCAUGGUUCUCUUACAUAUUGUAUCAAAGUGCCAUGAAGAAGGCUUGGAUAGUUAUCUAAGAUCAUUCAUAAAGUAUAGCUUCCGACCUGAAAAACCGAGUGCUCCUCAGGCCCAGCUGAUACAUGAAACCCUGGCUACUACGAUGAUAGCAAUAUUGAAACAGUCUGCAGAUUUUUUAUCAAUAAACAAAUUGCUAAAGUACUCAUGGUUUUUCUUUGAAAUAAUUGCAAAGUCAAUGGCCACAUACUUGUUGGAAGAGAAUAAGAUUAAGCUUCCCCGAGGCCAGAGAUUUCCCGAGACAUAUCAUCAUGUCUUACAUUCACUGCUUCUUGCAAUAAUUCCCCAUGUGACUAUUCGGUAUGCGGAGAUUCCCGAUGAGUCCAGAAAUGUGAACUAUAGUUUGGCUAGCUUCCUGAAGCGCUGUUUGACACUAAUGGAUAGAGGAUUUAUUUUCAAUUUAAUAAAUGACUAUAUAUCUGGAUUCAGCCCCAAAGAUCCUAAGGUUCUGGCUGAAUACAAGUUUGAAUUUCUGCAAACAAUUUGCAAUCACGAACAUUACAUUCCUCUGAACUUGCCAAUGGCAUUUGCAAAACCUAAACUGCAGCGGGUUCAAGAUUUUUUUUCAUUUGCGGUGGACCGUUUGACUUCAGUAGAUUCAAAUCUUGAAUACAGUUUAUCAGAUGAGUAUUGCAAGCAUCACUUCUUGGUUGGUCUACUUCUGAGGGAAACUUCCAUUGCUCUUCAGGACAAUUAUGAGAUCAGAUAUACAGCUAUCUCUGUUAUAAAGAAUCUUUUGAUAAAACAUGCAUUUGACACAAGAUACCAGCACAAGAACCAACAAGCCAAAAUAGCACAAUUGUACCUCCCCUUUGUUGGACUACUUUUGGAAAAUAUACAGCGAUUAGCAGGUCGAGAUACCUUGUAUUCUUGUGCAGCCAUGCCUAAUUCUGCAUCCAGAGAUGAGUUUCCAUGUGGCUUUACUUCACCUGCCAAUAGAGGGAGUCUGAGCACUGACAAAGACACCGCUUAUGGGUCUUUUCAAAAUGGACAUGGAAUUAAGAGAGAAGAUUCAAGAGGUUCCCUCAUCCCAGAAGGAGCAACAGGAUUUCCAGAUCAGGGCAACACUGGUGAAAAUACCCGACAGAGUUCUACAAGGAGUAGUGUAUCCCAGUAUAACCGCCUGGAUCAGUAUGAAAUCAGAAGCCUCCUGAUGUGCUACCUGUAUAUAGUAAAAAUGAUUUCAGAAGAUACUCUCUUAACUUACUGGAAUAAAGUAUCACCUCAGGAGCUCAUAAACAUUCUUAUACUUUUAGAAGUAUGCUUGUUUCACUUUAGAUAUAUGGGGAAAAGAAACAUAGCAAGGGUGCAUGAUGCCUGGCUGUCAAAACACUUCGGAAUAGACCGAAAAUCGCAAACCAUGCCUGCUCUUCGAAACAGAUCAGGAGUAAUGCAGGCCCGGCUUCAGCAUCUUAGUAGCCUAGAAAGUUCAUUUACACUUAAUCACAGUUCUACAACAACUGAAGCAGACAUUUUCCACCAGGCACUUCUUGAAGGCAAUACAGCUACUGAAGUUUCCCUAACAGUACUAGACACCAUAUCAUUUUUCACUCAGUGCUUCAAGACCCAACUUUUAAAUAAUGAUGGCCAUAACCCAUUAAUGAAAAAAGUGUUUGAUAUACAUCUUGCUUUUCUUAAAAAUGGACAAUCUGAAGUGUCGCUGAAACAUGUAUUUGCCUCACUGAGAGCUUUCAUCAGUAAGUUUCCUUCAGCAUUUUUCAAAGGAAGAGUAAACAUGUGUGCUGCAUUUUGCUAUGAGGUUUUAAAGUGCUGCACAUCGAAGAUUAGCUCAACCAGGAAUGAAGCAUCUGCACUUUUGUAUCUUUUGAUGAGAAACAACUUUGAGUAUACCAAAAGGAAAACCUUUUUGAGGACACAUCUACAGAUAAUAAUUGCUGUAAGCCAACUGAUAGCUGAUGUAGCACUAAGCGGAGGAUCAAGAUUUCAGGAGUCUUUAUUCAUUAUCAAUAAUUUUGCAAAUAGUGACAGACCUAUGAAGGCAACUGCCUUUCCCGCAGAAGUCAAAGACUUGACCAAGAGAAUCCGCACUGUUCUUAUGGCCACUGCCCAAAUGAAGGAGCAUGAGAAAGACCCUGAAAUGCUAAUUGAUCUCCAGUAUAGCUUAGCCAAGUCCUAUGCAAGCACCCCAGAGCUCAGGAAAACCUGGCUUGAUAGCAUGGCCAAGAUUCAUGUAAAAAAUGGAGAUUUUUCAGAGGCUGCGAUGUGUUAUGUCCAUGUAGCAGCUCUAGUUGCAGAGUUUCUUCAUCGAAAAAAAUUAUUUCCUAACGGAUGUUCAGCGUUCAAGAAAAUUACUCCCAAUAUAGAUGAAGAAGGAGCAAUGAAAGAAGAUGCUGGGAUGAUGGAUGUCCAUUAUAGUGAAGAGGUCUUGCUGGAGUUGCUAGAACAAUGUGUGGAUGGCUUAUGGAAGGCAGAACGUUAUGAAAUAAUUUCUGAGAUUUCCAAGUUGAUCGUUCCAAUUUAUGAGAAACGUCGUGAGUUUGAGAAACUUACUCAAGUUUAUAGAACUCUUCAUGGAGCUUACACAAAAAUUCUGGAAGUUAUGCAUACAAAAAAGAGACUUUUAGGCACUUUCUUCAGAGUUGCCUUUUAUGGCCAAUCUUUUUUUGAAGAAGAAGAUGGAAAGGAGUACAUCUAUAAAGAACCAAAGCUCACUGGCCUCUCAGAAAUUUCCUUGAGACUUGUUAAACUUUAUGGUGAAAAGUUUGGUACGGAGAAUGUCAAAAUAAUUCAGGAUUCAGACAAGGUAAAUGCCAAAGAGCUUGAUCCAAAAUAUGCUCAUAUACAAGUUACUUAUGUGAAGCCUUACUUUGAUGACAAAGAACUCACAGAAAGGAAGACCGAGUUUGAAAGAAAUCAUAAUAUCAGCAGAUUUGUUUUUGAGGCCCCUUACACUUUAUCAGGCAAAAAACAGGGCUGUAUAGAAGAACAGUGCAAACGCCGUACAAUCUUGACAACUUCAAACUCGUUUCCUUACGUGAAGAAGAGGAUUCCUAUUAACUGUGAACAGCAGAUUAAUUUAAAACCAAUUGAUGUUGCCACUGAUGAAAUAAAAGAUAAAACUGCAGAGCUGCAAAAGCUUUGCUCCUCUACUGACGUGGACAUGAUUCAGCUCCAACUUAAAUUGCAGGGCUGUGUUUCUGUGCAGGUCAAUGCUGGUCCAUUAGCAUAUGCAAGAGCUUUCUUAAAUGACAGCCAAGCUAGCAAGUAUCCACCUAAGAAAGUGAGUGAGUUGAAAGACAUGUUUAGGAAAUUUAUACAAGCAUGCAGCAUUGCACUUGAACUAAAUGAGCGGCUAAUUAAAGAAGAUCAAGUUGAGUACCAUGAAGGGCUAAAGUCAAAUUUCAGAGACAUGGUAAAAGAAUUAUCUGACAUUAUCCAUGAGCAGAUAUUACAAGAAGACACAAUGCAUUCUCCCUGGAUGAGCAACACAUUACAUGUAUUUUGUGCAAUUAGUGGUACAUCAAGUGACCGAGGUUAUGGUUCCCCAAGAUACGCUGAAGUGUGAGGAAAUGCAGAUGUACGUGACAAUGAGACUGACCUUUCUCAGGAAUAUUUGGAGCUGUGCAAAUGUUAAAAUUUAAAGAUUUGAUAUACAUGGAGUGUUUCUUCUCGACACCAAAAUUUUCAUGUGUUCCAACAGGGUGCUUACAUAUUUGUAAAUAAGCAACUUGAAAGUGCCUGGAAAAUUGCACCACUGUGCUUGGUUUGUACUUUUUUAGGUAAAUCUAUAUGCUGAAAAGUAGAGCUCAAAAACAGUAGUUCAAUUUGCUUAAUUAUUGCUUAAAAUAAUGGUACUAUGUAAAAUUGUAUAAUGGAAUACAAUAAAAGGUAAAACUUAUUUGUAA